GCACUCUGCGCCCGGAGGACAGAGCGGCCCGGUCGCCGGCAUGGUUUCUCCGUCCUGCUGCAGCCGGCGGGAGGCAGCCAGUCCAGGCGCCCGCUAGCUUCGGCGGCGACCCAGACGGGGAAAGCGGAAGGAAUGUCGCGUGCAAGCAGGCAGCUGGUGUGGAAGAAUGGCGGUGAGCCAUUCAGUGAAGGAGCGGACCAUCUCUGAGAACAGCCUGAUCAUCCUACUGCAGGGCCUCCAGGGCCGGGUAACCACUGUGGACCUGCGGGAUGAGAGCGUGGCCCACGGACGCAUAGACAAUGUCGAUGCUUUCAUGAACAUCCGCCUGGCCAAAGUCACCUACACGGACCGUUGGGGGCAUCAGGUCAAGCUGGAUGACCUCUUUGUGACAGGCCGCAAUGUCCGCUACGUCCACAUCCCAGAUGACGUGAACAUCACCUCGACCAUUGAGCAGCAGCUGCAGAUUAUCCAUCGGGUGCGAAACUUUGGUGGCAAGGGCCAAGGCCGGUGGGAAUUUCCCCCAAAAAACUGUAAGUGAGGCCCUCAGCAAGCCCUGGCCCCAACUCGGAGUCCUCCAGUGAUCUCCGGAGCUAGUUCCCUGCCCUCACACCCUGUCUGGUACCCGAGAAGAAAGCAGGGCCAGGCCAGAAGCUGGUGUCCAACAGACACCACCUGUCAAAGCUGCCUUUCACAGGGUUCCACCUCCCAGACUCACUCUGGGACCCAGAAUCCUAUAUGUGGCCUUGGGGUAGGUGACAAUCCCCCUUUUUGAUGAUCUGAAUCUCUGACUUAUUGAUUAUGGAACCUGUCAAGUAGUUUUCAACUCUCCCAGUGAGGAUAAUUAAACAUGCUCAGCCUGA